GAGAAGUAGCGCGCGCUGGGCAAGCAAGACGCUUUCCAAGUUGGGCGCGUCCCAGAGCUCACAGCCCGGUGUCCAGAGUGAGGCGGGGCUGAUGGGGGUCGCGGAAGCUGCCGUCGCUUGUGUCCAGAACCCGUCUUAAAAGAACCCGGGCCAGCAUCCCCAGUCGCGCGCCCUCGGCCCGCGUGAGCUCUCCGAUGCCUGCUCUGGCUGUGGCCCGGGUGGCCCGCCCGCGGGGGGUGCCAGAGGGGGCGGGGGAGGAGGAGGAGGCGGUGUGAUGGCCCUGGACGGCGAGCUGGGGGAGCAAGAGGAGGAGAAGAAAAAGAAGAAGAAAAAGAAGAGGAAGAAGAAGAAGGAGGAGGAGGAGGAGGAGGAGGGGGCCGAGAAGAGCAGCUCACCCUUCGCAGCCGCGAUGGGGGAAGACGACGCCGCGCUUCGGGCUGGCAGCAGGGGGCUCUCCGACCCGUGGGCAGACUCAGUGGGAGUGCGACCCCGCACCACGGAGCGCCACAUCGCCGUACACAAGCGGCUUGUGCUGGCCUUCGCUGUGUCCCUCGUGGCAUUGCUCGCGGUCACAAUGCUCGCUGUGCUGCUCAGCCUGCGCUUCGACGAGUGCGGGGCGAGUGCCACGCCAGGCGCCGACGGUGGCCCCUCAGGCUUUCCGGAGCGCGGCGGCAACGGGAGCCUCCCUGGAUCGGCCCGGCGCAACCACCACGCAGGCGGGGACUCCUGGCAGCCCGAGGCGGGUGGGGUGGCCAGUCCGGGGACCACGUCGGCCCAGCCGCCGUCGGAGGAGGAGCGGGAGCCGUGGGAGCCGUGGACGCAGCUGCGCCUGUCGGGCCACCUGAAGCCGCUGCACUACAAUCUGAUGCUCACCGCCUUCAUGGAGAACUUCACCUUCUCCGGGGAGGUCAACGUGGAGAUCGCGUGCCGGAACGCCACCCGCUACGUAGUGCUGCACGCUUCCCGAGUGGCGGUGGAGAAAGUGCAGCUGGCCGAGGACCGGGCGUUCGGGGCUGUCCCUGUAGCCGGUUUUUUCCUCUACCCGCAAACCCAGGUCUUAGUGGUGGUGCUGAAUAGGACACUGGACGCGCAGAGGAAUUACAAUCUGAAGAUUAUCUACAACGCGCUCAUCGAGAAUGAGCUCCUGGGCUUCUUCCGCAGCUCCUAUGUGCUCCACGGGGAGAGAAGAUUCCUUGGUGUUACUCAGUUUUCGCCUACACAUGCCAGAAAGGCAUUUCCUUGUUUUGAUGAGCCAAUCUACAAGGCUACUUUCAAAAUCAGCAUCAAGCAUCAAGCAACCUAUUUAUCUUUAUCUAAUAUGCCAGUGGAAACUUCCGUGUUUGAGGAAGAUGGAUGGGUUACGGAUCACUUUUCACAGACCCCUCUCAUGUCCACAUAUUAUUUAGCCUGGGCAAUUUGCAACUUCACAUACAGAGAAACUACCACCAAGAGUGGGGUUGUAGUACGAUUAUAUGCAAGACCUGAUGCUAUCAGAAGAGGAUCCGGGGACUAUGCUCUCCAUAUAACAAAGAGAUUAAUAGAAUUUUAUGAAGACUACUUUAAAGUGCCCUAUUCCUUGCCAAAACUAGAUCUUUUAGCUGUGCCUAAGCAUCCGUAUGCUGCUAUGGAGAACUGGGGACUAAGUAUUUUUGUGGAACAAAGAAUACUGCUGGAUCCCAGUGUUUCAUCUAUUUCUUAUUUGCUGGAUGUCACCAUGGUCAUUGUUCAUGAGAUAUGUCACCAGUGGUUUGGUGACCUUGUGACGCCUGUGUGGUGGGAAGACGUGUGGCUGAAGGAAGGGUUUGCUCACUACUUUGAAUUUGUUGGUACAGACUACCUCUAUCCUGGCUGGAACAUGGAAAAGCAGAGGUUUCUGACCGAUGUUCUGCAUGAAGUGAUGCUGCUGGACGGUUUGGCCAGUUCCCAUCCAGUAUCACAGGAAGUGCUGCAGGCAACAGAUAUUGACAGGGUGUUUGACUGGAUCGCAUAUAAAAAGGGUGCUGCUUUAAUAAGAAUGCUGGCUAAUUUUAUGGGCCAUUCAGUUUUCCAGAGGGGUUUGCAAGAUUAUUUAACCAUUCAUAAGUAUGGUAAUGCAGCCAGAAAUGAUCUCUGGAAUACAUUAUCGGAGGCUUUAAAAAGAAAUGGGAAAUAUGUAAAUAUACAAGAAGUAAUGGAUCAGUGGACACUCCAGAUGGGUUAUCCUGUUAUCACCAUCUUGGGAAACACAACAGCAGAAAAUAGAAUAAUAAUUACCCAACAGCAUUUUAUCUAUGAUAUCAGUGCUAAAACUAAAGCACUUAAACUUCAGAAUAACAGUUACCUGUGGCAGAUUCCAUUAACUAUUGUGGUAGGAAAUAGAAGCCAUGUGUCUUCAGAAGCAAUUAUUUGGGUGUCUAACAAAUCAGAGCACCACAGAAUAACUUAUUUGGACAAAGGAAGCUGGCUGCUGGGGAACAUCAAUCAAACUGGCUAUUUUAGAGUCAACUAUGACCUAAGGAACUGGAGAUUAUUAAUUGAUCAAUUAAUCCGGAAUCAUGAGGUUCUUUCUGUCAGUAACCGAGCGGGCUUGAUCGAUGAUGCCUUCAGCCUAGCCAGGGCUGGCUAUUUGCCUCAGAAUAUUCCUCUGGAGAUUAUCAGAUACCUGUCUGAGGAGAAGGAUUUUCUUCCUUGGCAUGCUGCCAGCCGAGCUCUUUAUCCUCUAGAUAAAUUACUGGACCGCAUGGAAAACUACAACAUUUUCAAUGAAUAUAUUUUAAAGCAAGUUGCAACAACAUAUAUCAAGCUUGGGUGGCCGAAAAAUAAUUUUAAUGGAUCUCUUGUUCAAGCAUCCUACCAACAUGAAGAACUACGUAGAGAAGUUAUAAUGCUGGCCUGCAGUUUUGGCAACAAGCACUGUCACCAACAGGCAUCAACACUUAUUUCAGAUUGGAUUUCCAGCAACAGGAACAGAAUACCACUAAAUGUUAGAGACAUCGUAUACUGUACAGGAGUGUCACUACUGGAUGAGGAUGUCUGGGAAUUCAUAUGGAUGAAAUUCCAUUCCACCACAGCAGUUUCUGAGAAGAAAAUAUUAUUGGAAGCCUUAACUUGCAGUGAUGACAGGAAUUUAUUAAACAGGCUUCUAAAUCUGUCACUGAAUUCUGAGGUGGUGCUGGAUCAAGAUGCAAUUGAUGUCAUAAUCCAUGUAGCUCGAAAUCCACAUGGUCGAGACCUUGCCUGGAAGUUUUUCAGGGAUAAAUGGAAGAUAUUAAAUACCAGGUAUGGAGAAGCAUUGUUUAUGAAUUCCAAACUCAUCAGUGGUGUCACAGAAUUUCUUAAUACUGAAGGUGAACUCAAAGAGCUCAAGAACUUCAUGAAAAACUAUGAUGGGGUAGCUGCUGCUUCUUUCUCACGAGCUGUGGAAACUGUCGAAGCCAAUGUGCGCUGGAAAAUGCUUUACCAAGACGAGCUUUUCCAAUGGUUAGGAAAAGCUCUAAGACACUAAUAUAUGUAUCUUAUAAACAAACAAUUCAACUCAGAAGUUUAUGAGAAGACACGCUUUUUGUGGAAUGAGGAAAAUGUACUACCUAGAAAAUGGCCAGAUUUUCAGUGUUAACGUGUGGGAGGAAUUUUUUUUUUAGUUUUUAUUUUUUGGUUUUGGGGGAUAUUUUUUAUUUGUUUCAUUCAUUCUGUUCUGUUUCUCUACUGGGUGUUCCUCUCUAAAGAAACUCUUGCAAGUGAAACUAGCCAUGAUUGCUUCAGCUGUACAUUCCUUGCUGUACAGGACCAAAUAUGAUAGUGAUGCAUGUUGAUGUUACAGUCAAUUUGGAAAAACAUAUUCAGAAUAUCUGUGCAUGGAUAUAUUGUCCUGCCUGUGUUCCAGCAUGCUUAUUUCAAACGUCCAGUGUUGUGUGUGAAUAUGUGUUACACCUAGGAUGGGCAUUAUGCAAAAGCACAAAGAUUAUAUAUGACAAUCAGUAUUGCAAUGAAAGAAAAACUAAAAACAGAAAUGAUAUUCUCAAUUUUGGGCAAUGUGAGAGGUAAAAUAGCCCUUGACAUGAUGAACAUCACUUAUUUCAGCACUUGGAUUGUCUGGCAAUGAUUACUGUGUUGCUAACUCAUUUUCUUUGAGUUAAAGCUGUGUAUACAUUUUAAAAGGCAUAUAGAUAGUGUAUGCAUAUGUAUAUGUACAUAGGGAAGCCCCAUAUGUAUAUAGUAUGUUGUACACUGCACAUGUACAAAGAAUGUCUUCAGAUCAAAGAAAAUUUAUCUCUUUUUAUAAACUUAAGGACAGUUGCAAAAGGCUUCAAGGAAUUUAUCUCAACAUUAUUCUUUCUAUGUCCUAACUAAAUUUCUCAACUGUUAUGAAUUUUUCAUCUACUUCUUGAACAGUGGUCUAUUCUGCUACAUGAAGAUGAAUACAAACAAAAUUUUUGUAUAAACUACUAUUCCAGUUCUCCUGUGUCAGUCUUGCCUAUAGAUUUUGCCAUCGUUUUCUGUCAAAGUUCCUUUUGCAUGAAACAAUUAUGCAAACUUAUAAUUAUUAGUGCUGAAAAAGAGUUUAUUUUCCAUCUUGUUUGUUUUCCUACCUUAUGCUGAGUAGUCCAGAGAGUUAAAAAAAUUCUCUGCAUGUUGGUCUUUUAAGUCUGUUUUGCUCUAAUCCUCCAUUAAGCGAGCAUACCUCAAGUGGGUCUAUUAGCAUUUAAUGACCUUUUGUGCCAGUUGUGCCAUCCCUUAAGAUGAAAAGUUCCUUUUCUUGUGUUAAUGUACAAAGCUUUUCUUUUGGCACUGACAACUGUGUUCUACCUGGGAAUUUUGAAUAGCCAUUUUCAUGGCUGUGUGUUGUGUAACACAAAUGUUUUUAAAUGGUAUUCUCACCCAGUAGGCCAGCUCUCCAAACGUUGCUUAGAUGCUUCAAAAUUAGCAUAUUUUAAGUUUACCAGUAUAAAAUACCAAUGCAACUACUCUACAUAGCCAAAUGUUUGUAAAUCACGUCUUAUUUUCCUGAGGUUUUUCACUCCACCAAAUCUUACAAAUCAUUGAAAGAAAUAUAUUCUAACAGUACGCACUGAAUAGUGAAAAUAAUUAGACAUUUUAAGAACCAGAGCCAUAGAAUUAUUUUAAAUUAGUAGAAAAGAGGAGCUAUUUCCGAAUCUAUAGAAUAAAGUACCACCUAAAACUGAAUUUUAUCAUAUAAGCAAGUAAUACCUAUUAGUCAUACCUAAAUUUUUCAGCACUUCAUUCAAUUAAAAUACAUGAAUUUUAAAUAUUUUACAUGAUGUGAAUAGGCAUGAUAAUACUUUUAGUAUAAAAUCUAAACUUUUUCCAUUUAUCAGAAAUGAUAAAAUCCAGUUACCACAUAUCACGUUUAUAAAAUCCUUAAUUAAAUGAGUAACUUCUAAAAUAUAACAAUACUAAAUAUCACACUGCGAUGGAGGUCCCAAAUAUGUGGUCUAUCACCACUGAAUUCAUGUAAUAGAUAAGAAAAAAAUUAGAGGUGGAUGUCUUGUUUUGUGUCAUGAAUUACUAAAAUCUCUUAGUAGUUGUGGUAUAUUUUUGAGUAAAAUUACCAUUUCCAGAUUUGAGUUUGAAGGGCUUUUAUAGUUGUAUUUUCCUCCUCACUGUUAAUAAUCAUAAUCCUUUUUCAGUAUUUUAGUGGCCUUGAACAACUGGUUUAUCUACAAUCUCAAAUCCUAAGUGUAUAAUUAUGUGCAAUGUUCAAUACCUCAUAUAAUACUUGCUCAACAGUAUAGUGGUACCAAUGGCAUUAAGAUGGUGUUUUUGUUCUACAUAUUUUUCAAUAAUUUAUUCUUUCUAAUGUUGAAAUUAUAUCAGGCUUUACCGGUUUUUUUAGUUGUUUAAAUAAGUAAUAUUUUCAAAAGAAUAAAAUAACCAAUGAUAUCUCUUGGAAUAAUCUGUAAAACGUAGUUAUAAAAUUCUAUUUUCUACUUAGAGUUUUUAUCUUUUCUUUUUUGUCGGCUUUACAAAUUAUAUGUAUGCAUGAAAUAACUAACUGUUGAAAGUGUCCAACCUCCAGCCAUAGCAAUUUGCUGUGCCAAUAUGUGUACAAAAAAGUAGUUUCAAUUAGAAAGGACAACAUUAUUUAUCACAUUGAGUAUUAAACAUUUCCAGGUAACUCGUAAAUAAAAAGAUUUCCCCAUUUUUACACAUUUUUUCUUAAAAUUUUUCUAUAAUCUUUGAAGUUUCUAAAAUACACAAUCUCAACCUCUAAGACUAACAUCUACAAUACUAGGUCUAUUCUUGAGUUUCAAUAACAUGUAUUUUAGUUGGGUCAUAAACUUGCAUUAUUUUAUAUUAUCUCCAGGACAAUUAUAUCAUAGGACUAAGAUUUUUGUGAUAGUAUUAUUUACAAAUAUUAUAAGUAUAAUAUCUUGUGAGGCUAUUAUUAAGGUUAUGCCAUGUAUUGAUAAAAUGCAUUGCUUUCUCAAAGAACUGUUACACAUUUUGUUUUAUUUGACUCAUCACAAAAACAUAAUAAAUGUUGUGAGCCCUAAUAUUCUGAUGAGAAAACUGGGGCUCAGGUAGCAACAUGAGCUAUUUAAAACUACAAAAUAGGGCUGGGCACAGUGGCUCAUGCCUGUAAUCCCAGCACUUUGGGAGGCUGAGGGUGGGAGGAUCACUUGAGCCCAGGGGUUUGAGACCAGUCUGGGAAACAUAUUGAGGCCCCAUUUCUAUAAAAAUAAAAAUGAAAACUAGCCAGGCAUGGUGGUGUGCACCUGUUGUCCCAGCUACUGGGGAGGCUGAGGUGGGAGAAUUAUUUAAGUCCAAAAGUUCAGUGCUCUAGUGAGCUAUGAUCACUGUACUCCAGCCUGGGUGACAGAGUGAGAUCCUGUCUCUAAAAAAAUAAAAUAAAAUCACAAUGUUUGUUGUUAUUUUGGGAACCAAUAUAACAACCUAAGUCUAUCACAACAUCAUUCCCCAACUAAAAUAUAAAUAUAUGUUGAAAAUAUCUCUAUCGAUUGCAUUAAUUGGAGAUUUUCCAAAUACUAGACCAGCAUCAAAAUACACAGUUAAAUAUAUUUGCAAUAAUUCCAUUGUUUGUUAACUUUUGCAUUUCUAAUUUGCAGGAUGUUAAACAACUGGAUGAAAUGUUAUGAUUUAAUUUGGUCAGUAUAAAUAAUCAAAUAUUGGGACAAAUAAUUUAAUUCAUUUAGUUUAUUAAUUAUAUUUCCUGUCUGUAUCUUUUAUUGAACAUUGUUUAAACAUAACCUUAAAGUACUGAUAAUUUGCUUAAUUUUCAACACAAAUUUAUCUGACAAAUUCUGUCUAUAGUAACAGAUGGUCAGAAUGCAGAUAAAUUGUGUGCAUCUCAAUCAGUAAAAAUAAUAUUCAGUAAAAUGUCUAUAAAUCUAUGCAGAUUAAGUUGUGAAAAACAAUGCAAUUUUAGUACUACUGGAUUAGAUGCAGUAAAGGAAUCCCUAAGGAAGUUUACAAUAAUAUAUUUAAUUAAAAUCUACUGGCAAUUAGAAUUUUAAGGAAUUCUUUUCUAAGAAGUUGGAGAACCUAAAAUAGCUUGCUUAUUCGCCUGGGUACUCUCAUGAAGUAACCAUGUACACCUAAUAAAGAAAUAGUAAAAGCACAUAUAAUGAAAAAUAAUUAAGAUUUCUUACACCUGAUUUUUUCAUUAUCAGAGAUAAUUAUCAGAGAUAAUUUUUCAUUAUCAGAGAUCAUAGCUGAAUUAUCAUUUGACAAUACAUAAGAAUAUAUAUUGUAUAGAUACAAUAUAUAACUAUACUUAAAGAAAUAUUUAUUGAGCAUCUUUUAUUUCACAAGGCACUUAGUGAGGGAAAGGAAUACAGAGAUGAAUAUGGCCUGAAGGAAUGAACUCAUAUUACAAUAAAUGAAAAAGAAAAAGAAAUAAUGAACCAAGGGAAUGAGGGCAACAGGAAAAAUAAUUCCUUGCUACAGACGGGAAGUCAAUCAUUUUUAGGUAUACAUAAUAUUAUACAACUAUUUUUGUACACUAGUUCUCAAAACAUUUAUGAUACCUAGUAUAAUUUUUAUUGUUUGAUUUCCUAGUGCUUACUUGUGUUUUACAGAAAUAUGUUACAUUUUGAAAUUAUAAUAAAAUAAUAGAGUUUAAACUCUAAUAAUUGGAAUAUAAAUUGGGAUGGAAUUUAUCCUUAAGAAAAGCUGUUUAAACAAUUUAGUAGUAUUAGUAAGUUGCAGGAAUACUUUAAUCUACUUACGAAAAAGUAGUUCAAGUUUUCUAAAAUGGUUUCAGCAUACUAUCGGUAUCUCACAAUGUGUUAAUUUUAAGUUAAUUAUAUAUUCUUUAAAGCAGAUUAAAUAAUACUUGUCCUAAGCAUAAUUUAUUUGUUGAAAUUAGUAUAUGUGAACUUAUGAAAAAAUGUUCUUGUAAAUUAUUCUAGAAUCCCAAAUUUUAAUUAUAUAAGAACAACCUUUUGUUCAAUUGCUUUGAACUAAUGAUGAAGUUUUUUAAAAUAUUAAGUAUUUUAUUUAAUGUGAUAUAGAUUCAGGAAAAGUCUAACAAAAAUGUACUUCAGUAGUUUUAUUUUUAUUUUGUGAAAUUUUAUUUUAAAGUUUAGGUAAGGAAAGUUUUUAAACUGUCUUAAAUAUUUAAUAAAAGCAGUUGUUAAAAAUAUAUGUUCUAAUGUUAACUAUAUGACAUAUAUGCCAUUGCAUGCAUUUUGUUUUUUAAAUAGGUUUUUCACCACUGGCCCCACUAGUAGAUGAUUUUACCCCAGAUUUUGAAAACAUACCACUUUAAUGGCCUUUAUUUCAAAUACUUCGUACUUUAGGGAUAGUAUUUUGAAGAUGUUUAUCUUUUGUACAUUCCUAGUUCAUUUAUUAAUGUACUAAGAAAAAGAAAACAAAAUGACUGAUUCUUUUGUUUUGAAUUAAAUGUUUGUGCUGUAUUAAUGUUAAGUGAGUUAAGAUAAAGGGAAGCUACAAAAAUUUGAAUGCCUACUAAAUGCUAGGCACUUUAUAGGUGUCUUCUAAUAUAUGUCUAUUGGUAUCACAUCAAUUAAUAACCCUGUGAAAUGUCAUUAGCUCUAAUUCACCAAAGAGUAGAUGGAGGCAGAGUUGUUAUCAGUUUACAUAAUUAAUUAGUGGUAUUCACUUGGAUUCAAAACUCUGCAAACUGAAGCCUUAUAUAGCUCAAACUAGUCAUUAAUCUGCCCUCAGCAUGUAUGAAAACAUAAUGUUUAUCCGUACAGACCAUUCUCUAUAGCAGAUUUGAAUAGGUACUUAGCACACUUUAUCAUUGUCACUGGCUCUUUCGAAAGAAGUAUUAAUUUGUGCAUUCUGGUUUACCAUUCAUUUCUUAACAAAGUUGCUUUAUACGUUCCAUAAAAAGUUUUCAUGAAAACAUUUUACAUUAGCAUGUUGUGUAGUGGGUUUUAAGUUAUAACAGGUAAUUAACAGAUAUUUCGGCCAACGAGACACACACACACAUGAAAAAAAUAAGUGAAAAGACAGAAUAAAUUGCAAAGGUUUUACGAGUGGACCACAAAGUUAAGGUUAAACUUCUGUCUUUGCAUGUGGAGGAGACAUAUUAGUCUAGCCAGAACUUUCCUUUUGCUUAGCAGUGAGGUCAGAGAAGUAUCUCUGUCAUUCUGCUUAGAAGUAUACAUGGACUGCAAUUGCUUAAUUUACUUAAACUUAACAUUUUCAAUGGGUUUGCUGUGUGAAGAUACAGUCUAAGAUAAGUGCUUUGACUUGCCUCUGCAGAGGUCAACUUAUUUCUCAUCACACACAUUUUUCUUAUGUCAUAUAAGUAAAGGAAAGAGUGAAACGUUUUAUAGAAAAUAUUACAGUGGAGUUAAGAACAUCUGCCUCAAAUGUACAGUGCAUUUACUUUUUAAGUUAAUCAUUUAGUAGCUACCCUUUUAACCUCUACUAUGUUCACAGUAUUGCAUUUGCUCUUGUAAACAAUUUUGUUCCCACCUUUACAUAGCGUAUGACCUACUCAGUGAGAACAUUCAUUAUUAAGUUUUUGCUAUUAAUUUUCAUUUAAAAUAGGUUUAUUAACUAGCAAAUCUCAAAUGCAAAACAUUUUUGAGUGAAUUUUUCCUCAAAUGUUGUAUUCUACCUUUCAAAAUAUUGUGUAACAGCAAUUCCACAUUAUCCUUUUGAAUGCUACCUAUAUAUUGCCACAUAUAAAGAUAUUUUUCAUUUUUCAUUUUUCAUUGCUAUCUUUUAAUCCCUUUGCAUUUUGAUAAUAUCGAAAACAGAUUAGGGCUGAAAAACUAAAAAAGAUUAGGGCUUGUAUUAUGCAUUGUCUAGUUACUUGAACAAUAAGAGAAAUUCUAUCUUUGAGCUUUCAUAAUUGGCUUUCUGGACACCACUGAGUUUAUUAGAUAAUCUUUAAAAAUAUUAUGAACUAUUUUGAGUGGACCUAAAUUUAUUCAGUAAUAAAGUUUACUUUCCUAAAUCCAUUCCCCAAGUGAACAGGCUUAUUUAAAAUAUGUCAUAUAAAAGCACUUUUCCUUUCUAACAUUUUAUGAUUUAGGAAUUAAAAAGUAGCUGUUCUUUCAGUAAAUAAGUGUUAAUAAAGCAGUGACCAAAUAAAUAACCUUUUGUUAGUUUAGCAGAUAAAUGUUUUCAAUGUAUGCCUUUAAAAUUAUUCAGUAAAAAUUGAAUUAGUACGUAUUCAACAUGAAAUUUUUAGUCUUUUCUGACCAAGCACUAAUAAAAUUGAUUUCCCUAAAUGAGAAAAUUUGUCUUCUGUAUUUUAAGCAGAAAAAAUAUGAAUUCUGCCUCUGAUAAUCAAAUUUUGUACAGCAAUGUGUAAUGUGUCACAAUUUAAAAAGUUUUAAUUUUCUGACAUGCAGAUAAGGCCAAAAUAAAUAAUACCAUCUGUUUUUUUCACUUGAAAAUACAUUUUUAAAAUUUUGAGUAUAUAUAUUAUAGAGGUCCAUGCAAAUGGAAAAAAAUUAUUCUCUUCUGACAUGGACUUUUUCAUGACUAUACACAUGCUGAGGCUAGAAUAAAAACAUAUAUUUGUGCUAUAUUGUAAAAAUAAAAACAAUUUGUUCUCCUUUCUAAUUAUAUGCCUUUAGAAUAAAUGAAAUGAUCUGCA